GUAACUGAAACUGUAGAAAGUGAAAUCGCAGAUAAGAGGGGGGACUACUGUAUUAGGUUCUAGCAUAUGCAUCUUGAUCAUCAUUCAGACCAUACCACAUGGUCUUCUGAGUGUGAGGGUAACCAGAUGAGUGAGAAUUUAGGCUAAAUGGGGACGGUUUGAAACAGCUGCUGGGCAUUGGGGAAGGCAGCUGAUUAGGACAAAUAUAGAGAUGGUGAACUUGGGCUUGUAGCAUUGUGGUAUUUUGGCUGGGGAACAGAGGGAUUUCUGAAACUUAUCCUUGAUCAUGGUCGCCUGUCACCAUGAGGGAGAUAAUAUGCCCAAGGAACAAUGGCAAGUGGGGGUCAAAAAUCUGAAUUUCUAUCUAGUCAGUUCUGGCUCUGGCCCCAAAUCCUAUAGUAUGUAAUUCUGGUAAAUUCUGCUGGGUUACCUUCCAAAUGUUCUCUUCUUCCUCAGCUUGUAAGGCCUAAGAGCAUCAGACUAAAGCAAGCCUCGAUGCUUGCUCUGUUCAUUUCAUCCAUCACAUCUAGCCCCAUAACCUAACUACCUCUCAACUUUACCACUGUGAUGGGAGAAGAGGACAUCCAGACACACCUGUGAUCAUCCAAGGGCAUGGAGGAAGAGAAAAGAAGACCGCAAGAGAAUGCACAUUCCCUCUCAGCAUCAGCACUAAUUUGCUUAAGAUGAUGCUGUAGGAGCACCAGGCCUGGCAGCCAUCAGCUGGGGAAGCAAUACCUUUCAAAGGAAAAUUAACAAAACAUCCCAGUCUACUCUCUUACGUUCAGCCUUUGGGAAAGAGAGACGGAGGGAAGGAGGGAAAGAGAGAGAUGAAGAUGUAUCCUGGUCUCUCCAACCUGAGAGUUCCUCUCCACUCCAGCAGUACAGAAGGGGAGGGCAGAAGAGAGAGCCACACCACACACACUCACUGUUAUUAUUUUACAUAGAUGAUUUCAUUAAGUAGUAAAGAGGUGCAAUCAGAGUCUUGGUAUUUAAUCAGUCAGAUACUUGGAGAGGAAUAAAAAAGCUUGCCUUCAGUGAUCCUUGGAUUAGGAGUGACAAGGUGGACUGGAGCUCCCUCUGAAGGACAGUGAACAACACUGAUCUCUUGUCCUCUGCUCCAAAACAGGAUGUGUGGCAGGUUCCUGCGGCGGCUGCUGGCGGAGGAGAGCCGGCGCUCCACCCCCGUGGGGCGCCUCUUGCUUCCCGUGCUCCUGGGAUUCCGCCUUGUGCUGCUGGCUGCCAGUGGGCCUGGAGUCUAUGGUGAUGAGCAGAGUGAAUUCGUGUGUCACACCCAGCAGCCGGGCUGCAAGGCUGCCUGCUUCGAUGCCUUCCACCCCCUCUCCCCGCUGCGUUUCUGGGUCUUCCAGAGAGCACCAGAAGACACAAGAAAGCAACCGAUAGCCUCCCAGUGGUGGAAACCAAAGAGCAAUUUCAAGAAGCAGUUCCAGGAAGAAGCUUAGCCCAGGAAAAACAAAGACCAGUUGGACCCAGAGAUGCCUGAGUUGGAGAUGAACUUUGGCCAACUUUCCUCAUCACCAUACUUAAAAUCCUGUCCAAGGAGGAGCUUAUUCACCAUUUUCUAUACAUGUGACAUAUGUAGCAGCAUAACCGACAACUGGGACUGCGCUGCCUUGACUCCACCUCUACAUACAAUGACUCAGCUAACCAGACUAAUAAAAGCCAUGUUUGCACCAUUGCUCAGGGAGGCAUUGCUUUGGGGAAUUAUUCCCAGUGUCCUCCUUACUUAUCGCAAGUAAUAAAAUCCCCCUGGGAAAUCCUC